GUCAGCUGAGAGCAUCCUCACUCGGUCAGUUCCUCGGGCGAGUUACGGGGACGACCUGCGGGAGCACGCGGGCAGUGGCCGGACGCUGAAGCCCAGGAGAGCGAUGGAGACGUAUGCGGAGGUUGGGAAGGAGGGCAAGCCUUCCUGUGCAUCGGUGGAUCUGCAGGGAGACAGCUCCUUACAGGUGGAGAUUUCUGACGCAGUGAGUGAGCGGGACAAGGUGAAAUUCACUGUUCAAACAAAGAGCUGCCUCCCUCACUUCGCCCAGACCGAGUUCUCAGUCGUGCGGCAGCACGAGGAGUUCAUCUGGCUGCAUGAUGCCUACGUGGAGAAUGAGGAGUACGCCGGCCUCAUCAUCCCCCCAGCCCCUCCGAGGCCAGACUUUGAGGCUUCGAGGGAAAAGCUACAGAAAUUGGGCGAGGGGGACAGCUCUGUCACUCGGGAAGAGUUUGCCAAGAUGAAGCAGGAGCUGGAAGCGGAGUACCUGGCCAUCUUUAAGAAGACAGUUGCGAUGCACGAAGUCUUUCUGCAGCGCCUGGCGGCCCACCCCACCCUGCGUCGAGACCACAACUUCUUUGUGUUUUUGGAAUAUGGACAGGAUCUGAGUGUCCGGGGGAAGAACAGGAAGGAGCUCCUCGGAGGGUUUCUGAGGAAUAUUGUGAAGUCCGCGGAUGAAGCCCUCAUCACGGGCAUGUCAGGGCUCAAGGAGGUGGAUGACUUCUUUGAGCAUGAGAGGACCUUCCUGUUGGAGUAUCACACCCGUAUCCGAGAUGCCUGCCUGCGGGCCGACCGCGUCAUGCGCGCCCACAAGUGCCUGGCAGACGAUUAUAUCCCUAUCUCAGCUGCGCUGAGCAGUCUGGGAACACAGGAAGUCAACCAGCUAAGGACGAGCUUCCUCAAAUUGGCAGAGCUCUUUGAACGGCUGAGGAAGCUGGAGGGCCGGGUGGCUUCCGAUGAGGACCUGAAGCUGUCAGACAUGCUGAGGUACUACAUGCGUGACUCACAGGCAGCCAAGGACCUGCUGUACCGGCGGCUGCGGGCACUGGCCGACUACGAGAAUGCCAACAAGGCGCUGGACAAGGCGCGCACCAGGAACCGGGAGGUGCGGCCCGCCGAGAGCCACCAGCAGCUGUGCUGCCAACGCUUCGAGCGCCUCUCCGACUCCGCCAAGCAAGAGCUCAUGGACUUCAAGUCCCGCCGGGUCUCCUCUUUUCGAAAGAAUCUCAUUGAGCUGGCAGAGCUGGAGCUCAAACACGCCAAGGCCAGCACCCUGAUUCUCCGGAACACCCUUGUUGCCCUAAAGGGGGAGCCUUAGAGUAGCCAGAGCUCAGCCAGACCCUAAUCUGGGAUCUCCAGUGACCAGGGUAUCCCAGACCCCUCUCUCCGGCAAGAUGUCUCCUUCCCUAGCAGUGCCACUAGCCACACCCUCACUCUGCCCCACAUCCUCUCAGGGAAAGCCCAAACCCCCUAUCACCACCACCACAGGUGCCAGGCCCUGCAAGACACAGGGCAGCAUGGGCAUCAUAACUGGCCACAGUCAGCAGAGCCCCAGGGACCCUGACACCUCUCCCCAGGAAGCUGAGGAACAGCCUCUACCCUCACCCAUAGCCCUGAAGGAAUCAUAGCUCACUUGAUCCCGGCCUGUUCUCCUUCGCAAAUAAAAACCCUGGUUUUGUAGCAA